ACUCCCUCUACAGCAAUCUCGGGAAAUUGGAGACUGACGCGGCUGCUCCUGCAUGUUAUUUAUUUUUCCUCUUUCCCUCCCGUGGAGACCCUCCUGUUGGAAAGAGAGCUGCAGCACGGGACAGAGACAGGCAGGAAGAAGCAGAGAGGACUCGGUGACGCCCCCACCGAGCAGCCCCUGGCCCACUCCUCCAGCAGGGGCCAUGAGCACCAAGCAGGAGGCCAGGAGAGAUGAGGGAGAAGCCAGGACGAGGGGGCAGGAGGCACAGCUUCGAGACCGAGCCCACCUGAGCCAGCAGCGCCGGCUCAAACAGGCCACCCAGUUCCUGCACAAGGACUCGGCCGACCUGCUCCCGCUGGACAGCCUCAAGAGGCUCGGCACCUCCAAGGACUUGCAGCCGCGCAGUGUGAUCCAAAGACGCCUGGUGGAGGGAAACCCGAAUUGGCUUCAGGGGGAGCCUCCCCGGAUGCAGGACCUGAUUCAUGGCCAGGAGAGCAGGAGGAAGACCAGCAGGACAGAGAUUCCAGCUCUUCUGGUCAACUGCAAGUGCCAGGACCAGCUGCUUAGAGUGGCCGUUGACACAGGCACCCAAUACAAUCGGAUCUCUGCUGGAUGUCUCAGCCGCCUGGGGUUAGAGAAAAGGGUCCUAAAAGCCUCAGCUGGGGACCUGGCCCCUGGGCCCCCAACCCAGGUGGAGCAGUUGGAGCUACAGCUGGGGCAGGAGACUGUGGUGUGCUCGGCACAGGUGGUGGAUGCUGAGAGUCCUGAAUUCUGCCUGGGCCUGCAGACUCUGCUUUCUCUCAAGUGCUGCAUCGACCUGGAGCACGGAGUGCUGCGGCUGAAAGCCCCGUUCUCAGAGCUACCCUUCCUGCCUUUGUACCAAGAGCCUGGCCAGUGACUGCUGUCUCAGUCAGUCCCCAGAGGGAAAGACCUUGCCUUAGAAGAAGAGGCGUGUGGGGAACGGGGGCUCUUGAAGCCAGGUAGCUGGGGACUAUGGUGUCUGCCCUUCCAAUCACCUCCCUGACCCCUGCUGUCCCAUUUUCCCCAGCUGGCCGCAUUCCUCUCUGCUUCUCAGCAGCUGUCCUACUCCCCAGGACGAGUUUUCACUAGAGGGCCCACGAUGCCAGGAUUCUGAUUCAUCUUCCUCCCAAGAAAAGCAAAGCCAAAUCAAGACCACAGAUAGGAACCUAAGCACAAUGGGGUGCCUGCUUGGGCUGGGUCGAAGGCUCUGCUGACUGCUGUCCUUGUCCAUCACCCAAUACCACCCCAAACACAACUCAACUUCCCACACCACCAUGUCUCUCACCACACCUUCUGGGCCUCAUUAUCUCCCACAACUAGACCGCCAUGCCUCACCAACCUAUGUCCCUGGACCUCCUGGUGUCUGCCUCUCGGAGUCUGUGCACAUCUGCUCACAGUUGAGUGGGGGAAGAAACAGCCAGAAUUCAAUACAACAAAGAGCGGGAGUUAGUAUAGGAAUGUCCAUCUCAUAAGGCUGAGAGCUAUUUUUUCCUGUGGCUGCAAAUGUCUGAAGCCAGUUAGUUUGAUUACCCUGUGCAAAACCUUGGACAUACUUCUGCUAUUAACGCUAUAGGUAUUUAUCCGUUUCCACUGGCUUUUUGUACCCACCGAGCCCCUGAGCCUUGCGUGUGUGUGUGUGGAAGAGCCUUGUAGAGAACUGCUCCUGUGAGGCAGACAGGACAGUGAGGUUGUCACCACUCAGACUUCACCUAUUCAGCAUUCUUUCUGAUUUCUAGAACUAUCCACCUCAUUAGGCCUUCUUCCUAUCCCCAUCUCUGGCCUCUUGAGCUUAAGCUUGUAUUGUCCUGGAAUCAGUGGCUUUCUAACCCCCUGCCAGGCUUUGCCAAAGCAAAAAGACAGAGGCUUUUUUUUUUUUUUUAAAGUUUGGGGUCUGUCAGGAGACAGAGGCUUUUUUGAAUUCACUGUGAAGAGAAGAACCCGAACCUUAAGACGCCAGAUCCCUGAGAGUCUUUCUGGCUGGUUUGAGUCUCUCAAAUCAUGGAUUAGGAGUAAAGAAAGAGGCCAGGCGCAAUGGCUCAUGCCUGUAAUCCCAGCACUUUGGGAGGCUGAGGUGGGUGGAUCACUUGAGGUCAGGAGUUUGAGACCAGCCUGGGUAAUAUGGCAAAACCCCAUCUCUACUAAAAAAUACAAAAAUUAGCCAGGUAUGGUGGUGAACACCUGUAAUCCCAGCUACUUGGAAGGCUGAGGCAUAGGAGUUGCUUGAACCUGGGAGAUGGGGGUUGUAGUGAGCCAAGUUCGUGCCAUCGGACUCCAGCCUGGGUGAAGGAGUGAGACCCUGUCUCCAAAAACAAACAAAAAAGGAGCAGAGAAAGACAGUGGUACAGCUAACCUGAACAAGGGAACUGGGACCGUUGGGCUGAAACAGUCUUGAGCCUGGGGUUGACUGGGUUAGAGAAGAACCGGGAUGCAAGGAGCUGCCUGUGACACCUGGCCUGCCCUUUCUCAGCUGCCUCCCCUGCCCUUUCUCAGCUGCCUCCCCUGCCCUCAGAAGGAAAGGAGAGGGCUCACUUAUCACUUGUGCCAUAGCACCUGGUCUCAAAAUCCUAAAAGCUUUCCUCGCCCUCACUGCCUUGCUCCACAAGGUCCACUUUCCUGGGUCUUGUGCUGUGCCUUUCCUUGUCUGCCUCCUGCUGCUUCUGUAACUGCAGACCCCAGGCCCAAUGGCAAGCCCUCGGCUCAGCUGCUUCUCCAUUGGAAUAAACUCUUGUUUCUCUA